CGGUUCCGGGCGUUACCAUCGUCCGUGCGCACCGCCCGGCGUCCAGGUGAGUCUCCCAUCUGCAGAGACGCGGACGCGCCGGCCCGCAGUUGGCCUGCGGAGCGCGGUGGACGGUUUGGCGCCCACCAGGCGAUCAAUACUUUGGAUUUUUAAUUUCUAGAUUUGGCAAUUCUUCGCUGAAGUCAUCAUGAGCUUUUUCCAACUCCUGAUGAAAAGGAAGGAACUCAUUCCCUUGGUGGUGUUCAUGACUGUGGCGGCGGGUGGAGCCUCAUCUUUCGCUGUGUAUUCUCUUUGGAAAACCGAUGUGAUCCUUGAUCGAAAAAAAAAUCCAGAACCUUGGGAAACUGUGGACCCUACUGUACCUCAAAAGCUUAUAACAAUCAACCAACAAUGGAAACCCAUUGAAGAGUUGCAAAAUGUCCAAAGGGUGACCAAAUGACGAGCCCUCGCCUCUUUCUUCUGAAGAGUACUCUAUAAAUCUAGUGGAAACAUUUCUGCACAAACUAGAUUCUGGACACCAGUGUGCGGAAAUGCUUCUGCUACAUUUUUAGGGUUUGUCUACAUUUUUUGGGCUCUGGAUAAGGAAUUAAAGGAGUGCAGCAAUAACUGCACUGUCUAAAAGUUUGUGCUUAUUUUCUUGUAAAUUUGAAUAUUGCAUAUUGAAAUUUUUGUUUAUGAUCUAUGAAUGUUUUUCUUAAAAUUUACAAAGCUUUGUAAAUUAGAUUUUCUUUAAUAAAAUGCCAUUUGUGCAAGAUUUCUCAAA